AACCCCGACGUCCGCGCCCCGGCCGCCUGUUGGCCAUGGCGGGCCUGGGCCUGGGCUCCGCCGUUCCCGUGUGGCUGGCCGAGGACGACCUCGGCUGCAUCAUCUGCCAGGGGCUGCUGGACUGGCCCGCCACGCUGCCCUGCGGCCACAGCUUCUGCCGCCACUGCCUGGAGGCCCUGUGGGGCGCCCGCGACGCCCGCCGCUGGGCCUGCCCCACUUGCCGCCAGGGCGCCGCGCAGCAGCCGCACCUGCGGAAGAACACGCUACUGCAGGACCUGGCCGACAAGUACCGCCGCGCCGCACGCGAGAUACAGGCGGGCUCCGACCCUGCCCACUGCCCCUGCCCGGGCUCCAGUUCCCUCUCCAGCGCGGCCGCGAGGCCCCGGCGCCGCCCGGAACUGCAGCGGGUGGCAGUAGAGAAGAGCAUCACAGAAGUUGCUCAGGAGCUGACAGAGCUGGUGGAACAUCUUGUAGACAUUGUCAGAAGCCUGCAGAAUCAGAGGCCCCUAUCAGAAUCUGGACCAGACAACGAACUGAGCAUCCUGGGCAAGGCUUUUUCUUCUGGGGUGGAUCUUUCCAUGGCUUCUCCAAAGCUGGUGACUUCCGACACAGCUGCAGGGAAAAUCAGAGAUAUUCUCCAUGACCUAGAAGAAAUUCAGGAAAAAUUACAAGAAAGCGUCACCUGGAAAGAGGCUCCUGAAGCACAAAUGCAGGGUUCUCUGUUGCCCAGGCUGGAGUGCAGUGGCACAAUCACUGCAGCCUCGAUCUCUCAGGCUCAGGAGAACUCCUGGAAGCCCCGUCUUCCUCCUCAUGCCCAUUGCCUGACCAGAGCCACCCUGCACUCAGGAGAGCUUCUCGGUUUGCUCAGUGGGCCAUCCAUCCAACCUUUAACUUGAAGAGCCUUUCCUGCAGCCUGGAGGUGUCCAAGGAUUCCCGUACAGUGACUGUGUCUCACCGCCCACAACCCUAUCGCUGGAGCUGUGAGAGGUUUUCUACCAGCCAGGUCUUAUGUUCCCAGGCCCUGUCUUCUGGAAAGCAUUACUGGGAAGUGGACACUAGGAAUUGCAGCCACUGGGCAGUUGGGGUGGCUUCCUGGGAGAUGAGCCGCGACCAGGUCCUGGGAAGGACUAUGGACUCUUGUUGUGUGGAAUGGAAGGGGACUAGCCAGCUCUCUGCAUGGCACAUGGUCAAGGAAACUGUCCUUGGCUCAGACAGACCUGGGGUGGUGGGCAUCUGGCUGAACCUUGAGGAGGGAAAGCUUGCCUUCUAUUCAGUGGACAAUCAGGAGAAGCUUCUGUAUGAGUGUACCAUCUCUGCCUCCUCUCCUUUGUACCCUGCCUUCUGGCUGUAUGGCUUACAUCCUGGAAAUUACCUGAUAAUAAAGCAAGUAAAGGUGUAAGGUUUCCUAAGGGAUUACAACACAGUGGUUUCCUGGUCUCUCUCCCUGUCAUCAAUCAGGGUAGUAACUUGACUUAAGAAUACCACUUUUUAGAAAAAUUACGAUAGAGAUGGGAUCUCACUAGGUUGCCCAGGCUGGUGUCGAAUUCCUGGUCUCAAGCAGUCCUCCCACCUCAGCCUCCCAAGGUGCUGGGAUUACAGGUGUGAGCCACCACACCUGGCCAAGAAUACCACUUUUGAAGUUAAUCCUUUUGUGUGAUACAGGAUGAACUUGGGAUGUUUGAACCCUGGACAUUCCAAAUAAAGAAUAGGCCCCUGCCUGGCUCCUGGGAGAUAACCUCUAAGCCAUUAGAAUAUCUUGCCUGAUAAGAGUGUUUUUGUUUACCUGUGGGCCUUGGGCCAUGCAGUAUCAGCUUGACCUUGCAAGGUCAAGCUGAGGAGACUAAGUUAGCCAUGUGGGCAGUGAAGCAUGCCAAUGUGAUCAAUCCCUAGUAAAAGCCCUGGACACCUAGGCAUGGGUGAGCUACUCUGGUUGGUAAUACUCUGUGCACACAUCAUUGUAGCCACACAUCAUUGCUGGGAGAAUUAAGCAUUAUCCUGAAGACUCUGCCAGGAGAGGAUAAUUGGAAGUUCUCUUGGACCUUACCUUAUGUGCCUUUCUUCAUUGCUGAUUUUAAUCUGUAUCCUUUCACUGUAAUAAACUGUAACUAUGAGUGCAACA